GCCCUCGGACUCGGCUCCCGCUGCGAGCGGCCGCCCUGCCCGCGCACCGCGCUCAGCGCCCACCGCCGGGCUUCCCGCGCCGGACCCAGUACCUCGGCUCCCCGGGGCCGGACCGAGGCCGCAAGCAGCGCCGCGGGGUGUGGGGCGGACCCAGGAGAUGAAAUGACAACGUCAACCCUCCAGAAAGCCAUUGAUCUGGUGACGAAAGCCACAGAGGAGGACAAAGCCAAGAACUACGAGGAGGCGCUGCGGCUGUACCAGCAUGCGGUGGAGUACUUCCUCCACGCUAUCAAGUAUGAGGCCCACAGCGACAAGGCCAAGGAGAGCAUUCGAGCCAAGUGCGUGCAGUACCUAGACCGGGCCGAGAAGCUGAAGGAUUAUUUACGAAGCAAAGAGAAACACGGCAAGAAGCCAGUCAAAGAGAACCAGAGUGAGGGCAAGGGCAGUGACAGUGACAGUGAAGGGGAUAAUCCGGAGAAAAAGAAACUGCAAGAACAGCUGAUGGGUGCCGUCGUGAUGGAGAAGCCCAACAUACGGUGGAACGACGUGGCCGGGCUGGAGGGGGCCAAGGAGGCCCUCAAAGAAGCUGUCAUUUUGCCAAUCAAAUUCCCACACUUGUUCACAGGCAAGCGCACCCCCUGGCGGGGGAUUCUGCUGUUCGGACCCCCUGGCACAGGGAAAUCCUACCUGGCCAAAGCCGUGGCAACAGAGGCCAACAACUCCACCUUCUUCUCUGUGUCCUCCUCAGAUCUGAUGUCCAAGUGGCUGGGGGAGAGUGAAAAGCUGGUCAAGAACCUGUUUGAGCUGGCCAGGCAGCACAAGCCCUCCAUCAUCUUCAUCGAUGAGGUGGAUUCCCUCUGCGGGUCCCGAAAUGAAAAUGAGAGUGAGGCCGCCCGGAGGAUCAAAACGGAGUUCUUGGUCCAGAUGCAGGGGGUGGGGAAUAACAAUGAUGGGACUCUGGUUCUUGGAGCCACAAACAUCCCAUGGGUGUUGGAUUCGGCCAUCAGGAGGAGGUUUGAAAAACGAAUUUAUAUCCCCUUGCCGGAGGAAGCUGCCCGCGCCCAGAUGUUCCGGUUGCAUCUCGGGAGCACUCCCCACAACCUCACGGAUGCAAACAUCCACGAGCUGGCCCGGAAGACGGAAGGCUACUCGGGCGCGGACAUCAGCAUCAUCGUGCGGGACUCUCUCAUGCAGCCCGUGAGGAAGGUGCAGUCGGCCACACACUUCAAAAAGGUCUGUGGCCCCUCUCGCACCAACCCCAGCAUGAUGAUUGAUGACCUCCUGACUCCAUGCUCACCAGGGGACCCAGGAGCCAUGGAGAUGACUUGGAUGGAUGUCCCUGGGGACAAACUCUUAGAGCCUGUGGUUUGCAUGUCGGACAUGCUGCGGUCUCUGGCCACCACCCGGCCCACGGUGAAUGCAGACGACCUCCUGAAAGUGAAGAAAUUCUCAGAGGACUUUGGGCAAGAGAGUUAAAAGCUGCUUCACUUGGGCAAUGGUGAAGGUGGGAGGUUGAUUGGGGCAAAUCCAGGCACUCCCCAUGUCAACAGCCAGACAGGGCUCCAGGGCUUGUCCCAGUCAAUACAGAGUUCCCUCUGCUGUCUGGCCGUCUGCCAGGGAGCCAGAAGGAAGGGCCUUGCAGCCACAGAGACACUCCACUGCCCUGGGGCACACAGUGGACACUGCUCUUCCUACUUCCUCCUCUCCUGGAUGCUCAUCAGCUCCUUCUGCCUCCCCCCCUUUUUUUUCCAUCUUUUGUUCCCCUAAAUUAAUGCUGCUUGGAUUUUCAUCUUAUUUAUAAAGAUAAAAUCACCUGGAAGUGUCAAGGAGUGGGGCGGGGUGGCGGGGGAGAAGCAGCCGUGCUGCCAGGUCACCCAGACCUCCAGACAGCCGGCUAGCCCCACUGCCCGUUCCUUUUACGCCCAAGUUUUGCUCCUUGAGAGCAGAUUGGCUGAUGCCCCUGCAACCCCAGCCCAAGCUCUGCCUCAAAGACCGAGUGACAUAAGCCAUUCCCACCCUCCUAGGUUCACAUCCAGGGCUGUGUCUUCCUUGGGGGAGGAGAUGGUGUCGUUUAGAUCAGGGUAAGGCAGUCAGGCGGGUGUUCACCACUGCCUUUUCUUCCUCUGAGCGUGAGAACACUGAACCCAGCCACUGCCCCUGGGUCCCUGUCCUGGAAAUGGUCUAAUAAAUCCUUUUCCCUUCUUGAGCUACCCAAGUGAUCUCAUCUUUCCUUGACUCUUAACUGAGACUCUGAAGGGCCACCCUUGCUUCCAAUUAAAAGACCCUCUGGUUUUCUGUCUCCUCUCUUUUCUAAAGCAGAGCAGGAAACAGAACACUGCAGUUCUUAGGCCUGUUCUCCAGUCAGGUGUGCAAGGCCUCCUCCCCUUAAGGCCUCAGAAGUUUGGCUGGGGAUGUUUGUGGGAUCCAGACAGUUCUUGCCGUUGUUCGGCCUACAGAUCAGAGACUGCAAAGUGGGAGCCCUGCGUACCAGACCCGUCCUGCAGCUGUGUUUGUUUGGUUUGGUCUGCCGCUAACAUUUAAAAGUCGAGAGUUGCUGGGCGCGGUGGCUCACGCCUGUAAUCCCAGCACUUUGGGCCGCUAACAUUUAAAAGUCGAGAGUUGCUGGGCGCGGUGGCUCACGCCUGUAAUCCCAGCACUUUGGGAGGCCGACGCGGGCGGAUCACAAGGUCAGGAAAUCGAGAACAUCCUGGCUAACACAGUGAAACCCCGUCUCACUAAAAAUAAAAAAAUUAGCCGGGCGUGGUGGUGGGCGCCUGCAGUCCCAGCUACUUGGGAGGCUGAGGCAGGAGAAUGGCGUGAACCCGGGGGACGGAGCUUGCAGUGAGCCGAGAUCGCGCCACUGCACUCCAGCCUGGGCGACAGAGCAAGACUCUGUCUCAAAAAAAAAAAAAAAGUCGAGAGUUGACAUAAAAAUUCAGAAUUCUGACUUCUAGAAGAUUAAAUUAGGUAAUGUUGGGCCUGCGUCCUCAUGGGGCAGCCUGUCAGCGGCCACUAAGUAGAGGCUGCUCUGUACAGAAGGGGUCCCCCAUCCCCACUCAUCUGUGUUGCCUGCCCAGAUAGCCCCAUGGCCAUUUCAGUUUGCGACCCCCAACAGACCAAGGACCCAGAGCUGGCAGCCCUGGACCCACGUCCGGCAGGCAGUGAAGCUGCAGAGGCUGUCCCACGUUUACCCCAUGCAUAUAAACAGACCAAAGUCAAAGCACAUUCACACAGAAAGACCUGGCCUAGUAAAUGAAGCUUAUAGCCUGCAAAGGGCUUUGUUCCAACCUUCCCUCUCCAAAACCCAGUACUGCUCCUCUACCUUUCAAACCUGGUUGGGCCAGAACUGAUUACAUGGCCAACUCUUGGCUCACACUGGGCUUGCACUGGGCCAUUUCUUUGCUCUGGUUCAGAGCCUCUGCAGAAGUGAGCUAACUUUGGAUCAGUAGCUCCAACACUUGGCUCCAGUGCUGGCAGGUUACCCCUCAACCAUAGCAGCUGGGAUCUUUGUGGCUUGGGGGUGCUUGUGUAAGUUCUUGGUUAUGUGCCCUCAGCCACCAGGAUAUGAACCGUGUCUGCAGAGCUUCACUUUAGUGAGCUUACAAGUUUUUAAAUUUUUACUUCUAGUUACAUUUACUUGAAUCAGAACGUUGUUUCCUCAUUCCUACUGCUUAAACACCUUGACAAGUCCUAGGGGUUAACAAAGGUUAGCAUGGCUAUGGUCCAUCCCUGUGCUCUAGUUAGAGCGUGAAGACACCUGACUUUCCAGUUGUCUCUCUCCAUGACCAGCAACAGGAACCACUGACGCUGAACUUUGGACAGUGGCCUCAGACUCUGGCUGCCAGCACACAACCUGCCAUCAUCGAUGUUAAACAUGCUGACAUGUGCAGAGGAGUUUCCUCCCUGAAAUGCUCUGAAAUUCACUUCUCUGCCUGGGGAUUCUGUUAUAAACCUUCUGCCUACAUUGGCUUUCACUGUGGAAGUUGAUUUCUAAAACUCUGAUGAGCUCACAACGUUGACAUGUAUAUGCGUUUUUUGUGAGUGCUUCCUGCUCAAAGUGGGAGAGAUUUUACUGGAAAUGCAAUAAAGUUUGCAUUUUAUUGCUA